UACCUCAUAUCUGGAGAUAUGUGUUUCCCUUCCCCUGCCUGCUUGUGAAAGCUAAAGCACUUGGGGCUGAGCCUGCAGACCACAGAUAAAGUUGCCAGAGUUUAUCGCCAUUGGGGUCUGACCACUCCCCAAGCUGAGACCAGGGCGUGGGAGAGAAGAGGAGCCCCUUCCUGGAAUCACGUCUGAGCAUCUGGCUAGAGCUGGCCCUGGCUAUUGGUGGUCAUAUGCCAUUUGUCACCAAUGCCUUACCAAAGGAACAGAUCUGUAACUACAGUGGAAUUUCAGUGGGAAAUAUGAGUGAGCAUGUGAGAACAAGAUCCCAAUCCUCAGAAAGAGGAAAUGACCAAGAGUCUUCCCAGCCAGUUGGAUCUGUGAUUGUCCAGGAGCCCACUGAGGAAAAACGUCAAGAAGAGGAACCACCAACUGAUAAUCAGGGUAUUGCACCUAGUGGGGAGAUCGAAAAUGAAGGAGCACCUGCCGUUCAAGGGCCUGACAUGGAAGCUUUUCAACAGGAACUGGCUCUGCUUAAGAUAGAGGAUGAGCCUGGAGAUGGUCCUGAUGUCAGGGAGGGGAUUAUGCCCACUUUUGAUCUCACUAAAGUGCUGGAAGCAGGUGAUGCGCAACCAUAGGUUUCAAGCAAGACAAAUGAAGACUGAAACCAAGAACGUUAUUCUUAAUCUGGAAAUUUGACUGAUAAUAUUCUCUUAAUAAAGUUUUAAGUUUUCUGCAAAGAAUCCUUA